GGUUCGGGCAGCGCUCUCCCGGGAGCGGCGGCACGCGCGGAGCGCCGGGUGCGGCCAUGCGGGGACCGGGCCCGACCCCGAGCCCGACCCCGAGCCCAAGCCCGAGCCGGAGCCCGAGCGAGACCCCGAGCCCGAGCCCGAGCGCGACCCCCGGUGCGGCGCGGCUACCCCGGCGGAGGCGGCGGGCGCGGGGCGCGCUCUGAGGCCCGGGGGAUGCGCCGCCGCCUCGACCAUGGGCGCCGCCGCCUCCAGGAGGAGGGCGCUGAGGAGCGAGGCCAUGUCCUCGGUGGCGGCCAAAGUGCGAGCAGCCCGAGCGUUUGGAGAGUACCUGUCCCAGAGUCACCCUGAGAACCGCAACGGCGCAGAUCACCUGCUGGCUGAUGCCUACUCUGGCCACGACGGGUCCCCCGAGAUGCAGCCGGCCCCCCAGAACAAGCGCCGCCUGUCCCUCGUCUCCAACGGCUGCUACGAGGGCAGCCUCUCAGAGGAGCCCAGCAUUAGGAAGCCCGCAGGCGAGGGCCCUCAGCCUCGAGUGUACACCAUCUCUGGGGAGCCUGCCCUGCUGCCCAGCCCUGAGGCGGAGGCCAUUGAGCUGGCGGUGGUGAAGGGGCGGCGGCAGCGGCACCCUCACCAUCACAGCCAGCCCCUGCGCGCCAGCCCUGGUGGCAGCCGGGAGGACGUCAGCAGGCCCUGCCAGAGCUGGGCGGGCAGCCGCCAGGGCUCCAAGGAGUGCCCCGGAUGUGCCCAGCUGGCUCCUGGCCCCACCCCUCGGGCCUUUGGGCUGGACCAGCCACCUCUGCCUGAGACCUCCGGUCGCCGCAAGAAGCUGGAGAGGAUGUACAGCGUUGACCGUGUGUCUGACGACAUCCCUAUUCGUACCUGGUUCCCCAAGGAAAAUCUUUUCAGCUUCCAGACAGCAACCACAACUAUGCAAGCCAUCUCGGUGUUCAGGGGCUACGCGGAGAGGAAGCGCCGGAAACGGGAGAAUGAUUCCGCGUCUGUAAUCCAGAGGAACUUCCGCAAACACCUGCGCAUGGUCGGCAGCCGGAGGGUGAAGGCCCAGACGUUCGCUGAGCGGCGCGAGCGGAGCUUCAGCCGGUCCUGGAGCGACCCCACCCCCAUGAAAGCCGACACUUCCCACGACUCCCGAGACAGCAGUGACCUGCAGAGCUCCCACUGCACGCUGGACGAGGCCUUCGAGGACCUGGACUGGGACACUGAGAAGGGCCUGGAGGCUGUGGCCUGCGACACCGAAGGCUUCGUGCCACCAAAGGUCAUGCUCAUUUCCUCCAAGGUGCCCAAGGCUGAGUACAUCCCCACUAUCAUCCGCCGGGAUGACCCCUCCAUCAUCCCCAUCCUCUACGACCAUGAGCACGCAACCUUCGAGGACAUCCUUGAGGAGAUAGAGAGGAAGCUGAACGUCUACCACAAGGGAGCCAAGAUCUGGAAAAUGCUGAUUUUCUGCCAGGGAGGUCCUGGACACCUCUAUCUCCUCAAGAACAAGGUGGCCACCUUUGCCAAAGUGGAGAAGGAAGAGGACAUGAUUCACUUCUGGAAGCGGCUGAGCCGCCUGAUGAGCAAAGUGAACCCAGAGCCGAACGUCAUCCACAUCAUGGGCUGCUACAUUCUGGGGAACCCCAAUGGAGAGAAGCUGUUCCAGAACCUCAGGACCCUCAUGACUCCUUAUAGGGUCACCUUCGAGUCACCCCUGGAGCUCUCAGCCCAAGGGAAGCAGAUGAUCGAGACGUACUUUGACUUCCGGUUGUAUCGCCUGUGGAAGAGCCGCCAGCACUCGAAGCUGCUGGACUUUGACGACGUCCUGUGAGGGGCAGAGGCCUCCGCCCAGUCACCAUCAGGCCACUCCCUCUGCACCGGGACCUGGGGCUGGGCCGCCUCGUGCUCCCCGGGACUGUGUGGCUCCGGUCUCGCCUGGAGCCACUUCAGGGCACCUCAGACGUUGCUCAGGUUCCCCCUGUGGGUUCCGGUCCUCGCUGCACCCGUGGCCGCAGAGGCUGCAGUCCCUGGGGGCCGGGAGGAUCCCGCCCUGUGGCCCGUGGAUGCUCAGCGGCCAGGCACUGACCUGCCAUGCCUCGCCUGGAGGCUCAGCUGUGGGCAUCCCUCCAUGGGGUUCAUAGAAAUAAGUGCAAUUUCUACACCCCCGAAACAAUUCAAAGGGAAGCAGCAUUUCUUGUUAACUAGUUAAGCACUAUGCUGCUAGUUACAGUGUAGGCACCCCGGCCCAGCAGCCCAGCAGCCCACAUGUGUUCAGGACCCUCCCUGCCCACCCCCUCCCUGCCGUAUCGAUCACCAGCACCAGGGUGGCCCGUGUGCGUGGGGCCAGCGUCGCCGGGCUGCCCAGCCUGGCUCUGUCUACACUGGCCGAGUCUCUGGGUCUGUCUACACUGGCCGAGUCUCCGACUGUCUGUGCUUUCACUUACACUCCUCUUGCCACCCCCCAUCCCUGCUUACUUAGACCUCAGCCGGCGCCGGACCCGGUAGGGGCAGUCUGGGCAGCAGGAAGGAAGGGCGCAGCGUCCCCUCCUUCAGAGGAGGCUCUGGGUGGGGCCUGCUCCCCAUCCCCCCAAGCCCACCCAGCACUCUCAUUGCUGCUGUUGAGUUCAGCUUUUACCAGCCUCAGUGUGGAGGCUCCAUCCCAGCACACAGGCCUGGGGCUUGGCAGGGGCCCAGCUGGGGCUGGGCCCUGGGUUUUGAGAAACUCGCUGGCACCACAGUGGGCCCCUGGACCCGGCCGCGCAGCUGGUGGACUGUAGGGGCUCCUGACUGGGCACAGGAGCUCCCAGCUUUUGUCCACGGCCAGCAGGAUGGGCUGUCGUGUAUAUAGCUGGGGCGAGGGGGCAGGCCCCCCUUGUGCAGAGCCAGGGGUCUGAGGGCACCUGGCUGUGUUCCCAGCUGAGGGAGGGCUGGGGCGGGGGCCGGGCUUGGAACGAUGUACGAUACCCUCAUAGUGACCAUUAAACCUGAUCCUCCACCGCGGCCGCCGCGUGGGUCUGUCCUCUCAGUGCUUUCCAGGGGCCUUCCUGUGCCCAGCUUCUGGGCCCACUCCUGUGAGGUCACUGCUGCAGGGCCUUCCUGCCUGGACAGAGUUGGAGCUAGGCCACUAGACCACCCCACAGGGCAUAGCCAGGGGGACCAGCACAGGAGGGGACGGAGAGGAGCUGCAGGAGGGCUGGGGGGAGGCUGCAGUCUCGGAGGGGGGCCUCGCCGGGUCUGGAGGGGACAGCAGAGACAGCCCGUUCCCCCUGCCGCCUGAGGGCACCAGGGAGAGGGCUGUAUGUCCCUCACGCCACACUGUGUGUGCAGUCAGCAGUGUGGCCACAGAUGGGGGCCACUCUCUCAACCUCAGGUGUCCUCAGGGCCCAGACCGCUGCUGGGCACAGCCAGGCUGGCUGCCAGCUGGUUCCCUGCCCCGUGGCUGGGGGACAGAGCAGCACGUAUCAGCUGGGCUAGGGUCAGGGGGCCACUGGUGCGCAGCCUGGCACAGCCUGGCAGGCUUGAGGCCCAGUGUGCUGGGGGUGGUCACACAGCCGUCAGCCACCUCCAGCUCUUCCAGGGCAUUCUAGAUGGGGUCCCGGGAGGGGGCAGGUUUUGGUGCCAAUUUGAGUGUAUAAAGUUUUAGGUAAAUACCAAA